ACAGUCACUCAGUAAGGCUGUGCUGGAGAGCAUAGGGAAGCAUUGAGCCUUGCAGGGUAAGCUGUGUUUGUAAGCUACAUUCAGAGUAUGACAGUUCUACUGAUUUCAGAGGGAAAUAGAUAGGAGUGGAUUUGUGCUUUAGAAUGAUCACUCUACUCUAAGACUAGGAAAUGAGUUGUGAGUACCAGAAACAUGCUGAGAUGAGAAUGGAUAGAGUCUUCAACGGAAAUAUGGAAAAUACCAGACAGGGUGAUUAAUAGGUAGGAUAGGUGAGAGUAGUCCAGGAACAAUCUACAGGUUCCUUACUUGGGUAAUUGGACAGAAGAAGGUACCAUUCAUUGAAAUAUGGAACAUGGGAGUAAGAGCUGGUUGGCGGUGGGGGAAAGGAAAAUGAGUUUAGUUUUCUAUAAAAGUAGAUGUGUUAAUUAGGUGUGUGUGUGUGUGUGUGUGUGUGUGUGUCUGCGUGUUCUCAGGAAGAAGUGCAUAUCAGGAUUGUAGAAGAGAUUGAGGAAACAAAAAUAAAGAGAUCUUACUUGAAAUCAUGAGAGUGAAGAGAGAGCCUAGAAAAAAUUUAUUAAUAUAAUCUUAGGAGAAAGGAGAACUUAAAAUGGAACUAUAAGGAUAGUCAGCAUUUAAGGGACAAGCAAAGAAAAAGAGGUAGAUGAAGGAUUUAUUAGUAUUUGUUUGCAAAACAGAGGGGUAAGAAGAAUAAAUAUAUGAAACAGGGCUGAAGCACAGUGCAACAAAAUGUUAGAUUAUGUGGAGUGCUCAGAGGAAAGGCAGAAUUGUGGAUUCCUGUCCCCCUGCCCCCCAGAAUCCAGAAUGUCUACACAAAAUAAUGUUGGCAUUCCCCAUGAAUGAAACUUUUUGUUGCCUUUGGAUUGCCUGUGUUUUCAAUUCUACACUGGCUCAGCAAGGGACAGAAAGCUUUCAGUGUGACAAUGGAGUCUCCUUGCCUCCUGACAGCAUUUGUGACUUCACAGAUCAGUGUGGGGAUAGCAGUGAUGAACGGCACUGUUUGAAUUAUGAAAGAUGUGAUUUUGAGGAUGGUCUCUGUCAUAUGACUCAAGAUCAGAGUCUGCAACCUAGUUGGACAAAGAGAAGUGGGAUGAUUGGUCUAUCACCUCCAUUUUAUGAUCACAAUGGUGAUGUGUCUGCUCACUUCCUCUCACUGGUUUCCAGAGUGGAUUCUAUUUCCUCAAGUUUAAGAAGCAGAGUUUUCCUUCCAACAAAUGAUCAACAUGACUGCCAGAUUACAUUUUAUUACUUCUCCUGCCAAGUGAGUGGCAAAUUAAUGGUUGGGCUUCAAACUGCAUGUGGAGGUCCUAUUCAGCAUUUAUGGCAAAACACAGCUGCACUCCCAAAUCAGUGGGAGAGAAAUGUCAUCAAAAUCCAGAGUUCACAGAGAUUUCAGGUUGUUUUUGAAGGUCAAAUGGCUUCAACGUAUGAACAGGAUGAAGUCAUUGCUAUUGAUGAUAUAUCUUUCAGUUCAGGCUGCUUGCCUGCCAAUGAUGGAAUUUUACUGUGUCAAGAAGCAUUGAAUGCUGAGCGGGAGCUAUGCCAUCCAGAUACAGAUCUCUGCAGAUUUGAUGCUACAGAUGAAGAGUUGAGAUUGUGUCAGGCCUGUGGGUUUGAAUUUGACAUGUGUGAGUGGACGUCAGAAGCAUCUGCUGGCCAAAUUUCCUGGAUGCGCACAAAAGCGAGAGAGAUCCCUGCAUUCGAAUCCACACCUCAGCAGGAUCAAGGAGGUGAUGAUGAAGGUUAUUAUGUAUGGGUAGGCGCUAAGCAUGGUUUCACUCUUAACCAUUUAGACAGCAGGGCUUACCUAAAUAGCUCUGUGUGUCAUUGCCUGGGCAAGAGCUGUCAUCUUCAAUUCUAUUAUGCAAUGGAAAGCAGUGUCCUGAGAGUAAGACUGUAUAAUAAUAAGGAAGAAGAAAUAUUUUGGACAUACAACAUAUCAACUCACAGCCAAUGGGUGAAAGCAGAUGUGUUAAUACCAGAAGAUCUGAAGACAUUUAAGAUUAUUUUUGAAGGGACUCUUUUGAGCCAGAGAAGUUUUAUUGCCCUUGAUCACCUCUGGGUCUAUGCCUGUGGACAGACCCAAUCCAGAAAGCUUUGCUCUGCAGACGAAUUCCCUUGCACUAGUGGCCAGUGCAUCGCCAAAGAAUCUGUCUGUGACUCUCGGCAGGACUGCUCCGAUGAGAGUGAUGAAGACCCAGCAACUUGCUCAAAGCAUCUCACCUGUGACUUUGAGUCGGGUUUCUGCGGUUGGGAGCCAUUUCUCACAGAAGAUUCACACUGGAAGCUGAUGAAAGGAUUGAAUAAUGGAGAGCACCACUUUCCUGCAGCUGAUCACACAGCAAACAUAAAUCAUGGAUCGUUUAUUUAUUUGGAGGCACAGCGCUCCCCCGGGGUGGCCAAGCUUGGAAGUCCUGUUCUUACAAAAUUGCUCACUGCCUCUACCCCAUGUCAGGUGCAGUUUUGGUAUCAUUUGUCUCAACAUUCAAAUCUCUCAGUUUUUACAAGAACGUCUCUAGAUGGAAACUUGCAAAAGCAGGGCAAAAUAAUCAGAUUCUCCGAAUCUCAGUGGAGCCACGCAAAAAUUGAUCUCAUUGCAGAAGCGGGAGAAUCUACUCUACCUUUUCAGUUAAUUUUGGAAGCUACUGUUUUGUCGUCAAAUGCUACCGUUGCUCUAGAUGACAUCAGUGUGUCCCAGGAAUGUGAAAUUUCCUAUAAAUCACUACCAAGGACCAGUACACAAAGCAAGUUUUCCAAGUGUGACUUUGAAGCAAACAGCUGUGAUUGGUUUGAAGCAAUUAGUGGUGACCAUUUUGACUGGAUACGGAGCUCUCAGAGUGAACUUUCUGCUGAUUUUGAGCACCAGGCUCCACCUCGGGAUCAUAGUCUCAACGCAUCUCAAGGGCAUUUUAUGUUCAUUCUGAAGAAAAGCAGCAGCUUGUGGCAAGUUGCUAAGCUUCAGAGCCCAACUUUCAGCCAGACAGGACCUGGAUGCAUACUUUCCUUCUGGUUCUAUAACUAUGGCCUGUCAGUGGGAGCAGCUGAGCUGCAGCUACAUAUGGAAAAUUCUCAUGACUCAACAGUGAUUUGGAGAGUAUUAUACAAUCAGGGCAAACAAUGGUUGGAGGCAACCAUUCAGCUAGGGCGCCUUUCGCAGCCCUUCCAUUUGUCACUAGAUAAAGUCAGUCUGGGCAUUUAUGAUGGGGUCUCAGCUAUUGAUGACAUCCGAUUUGAAAAUUGUACUCUCCCUCUUCCUGCUGAGAGCUGUGAAGGGCUGGAUCAUUUCUGGUGUCGCCACACCAGGGCUUGCAUAGAAAAGCUUCGGUUAUGUGAUCUGGUGGAUGACUGUGGUGAUCGUACUGAUGAAGUCAACUGUGCACCUGAGCUGCAGUGUAACUUUGAAACUGGAAUCUGUAACUGGGAACAAGAUGCAAAAGAUGACUUUGAUUGGACCAGGAGCCAGGGUCCAACUCCAACACUUAACACAGGGCCAAUGAAAGAUAACACUCUGGGCACAGCUAAAGGACACUAUCUCUACAUAGAAUCUUCAGAGCCACAGGCUUUUCAAGACAGUGCUGCCUUACUCAGCCCAAUCCUUAAUGCCACUGAUACAAAAGGCUGCACCUUCCGCUUCUAUUACCACAUGUUUGGAAAGCGCAUUUAUAGGUUGGCAAUCUACCAACGAAUCUGGAGUGACUCAAGGGGACAGCUGCUGUGGCAGAUAUUUGGGAAUCAAGGCAACAGAUGGAUUAGGAAACACCUCAACAUUUCCAGCAGGCAGCCCUUUCAGAUAUUGGUGGAGGCUUCAGUGGGAGAUGGCUUCACUGGAGAUAUUGCGAUUGAUGAUCUGUCAUUUAUGGACUGCACCCUCUACCCUGGUAAUUUGCCAGCAGACCUCCCAACUCCACCAGAAACGUCAGUUCCUGUAACAUUACCUCCACACAACUGCACAGACAAUGAAUUUAUCUGCAGGUCUGAUGGUCACUGCAUUGAAAAAAUGCAGAAAUGUGAUUUUAAAUAUGACUGCCCUGACAAAUCAGAUGAAGCAUCCUGUGUUAUGGAAGUUUGCAGCUUUGAGAAAAGAAGCCUGUGUAAAUGGUAUCAACCAAUCCCAGUACAUUUGCUUCAAGAUUCAAACACAUUCAGGUGGGGGCUUGGGAACGGGAUCAGCAUUCAUCAUGGGGAAGAAAACCACAGGCCAUCAGUGGAUCAUACACAAAAUACCACUGAUGGCUGGUACCUGUAUGCUGACAGUUCUAAUGGGAAAUUUGGUGACACGGCUGACAUUCUCACUCCUAUCAUUUCACUCACGGGACCAAAAUGUACCUUGGUGUUCUGGACACAUAUGAAUGGGGCCACCGUUGGUUCUCUCCAGGUGCUCAUCAAGAAAGAUAACGUUACUUCUAAAUUGUGGGCUCAAACUGGACAGCAAGGUGCACAGUGGAAGAGAGCAGAAGUGUUUUUAGGCAUUCGUUCACAUACACAGAUUGUCUUCAGAGCCAAACGUGGUAUCAGUUACAUAGGAGAUGUAGCAGUGGAUGAUAUUUCCUUCCAAGAUUGCUCCCCUUUGCUUAGCCCAGAGAGAAAGUGUACUGAUCAUGAAUUCAUGUGUGCUAAUAAGCACUGCAUUGCCAAAGACAAGCUGUGUGAUUUUGUGAAUGAUUGUGCUGAUAAUUCAGAUGAGACUACUUUCAUUUGCCGUACCUCCAGUGGGCGCUGUGAUUUCGAAUUUGAUCUUUGUUCCUGGAAGCAGGAGAAAGAUGAGGACUUUGACUGGAACCUGAAAGCUAGCAGCAUCCCUGCAGCAGGCACAGAGCCAGCAGCAGAUCACACUUUGGGAAAUUCAUCUGGUCAUUACAUCUUUAUAAAGAGUUUGUUUCCUCAGCAGCCCAUGAGAGCUGCCAGAAUUUCAAGUCCAGUUAUAAGUAAGAGAAGCAAAAACUGCAAGAUUAUUUUUCAUUAUCACAUGUAUGGAAAUGGCAUUGGGGCACUCACCUUAAUGCAGGUGUCAGUCACAAACCAAACGAAGGUUCUACUUAACCUCACUGUAGAACAAGGCAAUUUCUGGCGGAGAGAAGAACUGUCACUGUUUGGUGAUGAAGACUUCCAACUCAAAUUUGAAGGUAGAGUUGGGAAAGGUCAGCGUGGAGACAUUGCACUUGAUGACAUUGUGCUUACAGAAAAUUGUCUAUCACUCCAUGAUUCCGUGCAAGAAGAACUGGCAGUGCCUCUUCCAACAGGUUUCUGCCCACUUGGCUAUAGGGAAUGUCAUAAUGGAAAAUGCUAUAGGCUGGAACAAAGCUGUAACUUCGUAGAUAACUGUGGAGAUAAUACUGAUGAAAAUGAGUGUGGUAGCUCCUGUACUUUUGAAAAAGGCUGGUGUGGCUGGCAAAACUCCCAGGCUGACAACUUUGAUUGGGUUUUAGGGGUUGGCUCUCAUCAAAGCUUAAGACCUCCCAAAGACCACACACUUGGAAAUGAAAAUGGGCACUUCAUGUAUCUGGAAGCUACUGCAGUGGGCCUUCGGGGUGACAAAGCACACUUCAGGAGUACCAUGUGGCGAGAAUCCAGUGCAGCCUGCACCAUGAGCUUCUGGUAUUUCGUAUCUGCAAAGGCCACAGGAUCCAUUCAGAUUCUCAUCAAGACAGAGAAAGGACUAUCAAAAGUAUGGCAAGAAAGUAAGCAGAACCCUGGUAAUCAUUGGCAAAAGGCUGACAUCCUGCUAGGAAAGUUAAGGAAUUUUGAAGUCAUAUUUCAAGGUAUCAGAACAAGGGACCUGGGAGGAGGAGCUGCAAUUGAUGAUAUUGAAUUUAAAAACUGCACAACUGUGGGAGAGAUCUCUGAGCUUUGUCCGGAAAUCACUGAUUUUUUGUGCCGGGACAAGAAGUGCAUUGCAUCCCACCUUCUUUGUGACUAUAAGCCAGACUGCUCUGAUAGGUCUGAUGAAGCUCACUGUGCACAUUAUACAAGCACAACAGGAAGCUGCAAUUUUGAAACAAGUUCAGGAAACUGGACCACAGCCUGCAGUCUUACUCAAGACUCUGAGGAUGACUUGGACUGGGCCAUUGGCAGCAGAAUUCCUGCCAAAGCAUUAAUUCCAGACUCUGAUCACACGCCAGGUAGUGGUCAGCACUUCCUGUACGUCAACUCAUCUGGCUCCAAGGAAGGAUCCGUUGCCAGAAUUACUACUUCCAAAUCCUUCCCAGCAAGCCUUGGAAUGUGUACUGUUCGGUUCUGGUUCUACAUGAUUGAUCCCAGGAGUAUGGGAAUAUUAAAGGUGUAUACCAUUGAAGAAUCGGGGCUAAACAUCCUGGUGUGGUCAGUGAUUGGAAAUAAAAGAACGGGAUGGACAUAUGGCUCUGUGCCUCUCUCCAGUAACAGUCCGUUUAAGGUGGCAUUUGAAGCUGAUUUGGAUGGAAAUGAGGACAUCUUUAUUGCUCUUGAUGACAUCUCUUUUACCCCAGAGUGUGUGACUGGAGGUCCUGUCCCAGUGCAGCCAUCACCCUGUGAAGCUGAUCAGUUUUCUUGUAUCUACACACUCCAAUGUGUCCCUCUCUCAGGGAAAUGUGAUGGACAUGAAGACUGCAUAGAUGGAUCUGAUGAAAUGGAUUGUCCUCUCAGCCCCACCCCUCCACUCUGUAGUAACAUGGAGUUCCCGUGCUCUACAGACGAGUGUAUACCUUCCCUCCUGCUAUGCGAUGGAGUGCCCGACUGCCACUUUAAUGAAGAUGAGCUCAUCUGCUCCAACAAAAGCUGUUCUAAUGGAGCUCUGGUGUGUGCCUCCUCCAACAGCUGUAUCCCAGCCCACCAGCGCUGUGAUGGUUUUGCCGACUGCAUGGAUUUCCAGCUUGAUGAGUCCAGCUGCUCCGAAUGUCCAUUAAAUUACUGCAGAAAUGGUGGGACUUGUGUAGUGGAGAAAAAUGGUCCUAUGUGUCGACUCCAAUGCCAGAUGAGCAGAAGACACUGGGACUGGAGUAGCUGAAGAAGAACGAAAAUGUCAGCUCACCUACUUAGUCGAUGAUCAACCUUCUGGAGGGGAAGAAAUGCUGCUAAAUUUGAGGCUUUUGUUGUUACGCAAGACUGAGCAUUUAAAUCACCAAAAUUAGGCCCAUUUUUGUGACUUAGAGUGCCCAUCACAUUAUUGGUUUACCCAAGAGUGAUCAAGGAAGUCAUGAGAUCUAGUAGAAAUGUUAUUCAAGUGUAGCAGGUUUAAAGAUCAUGGAAGACAAAAUGGAUUUCUAUUUUAAAUUGUAUUCGAAAAGUCAUGCUUGCGGAAUAUGGAGACUUAGAUCUUCAGCUCGGCAUUGUUCUGGAUUCUGUUGGUAAGAAAGGAAAAAAUACACAUGGGCUAAGCUCACAGCACUCUUUUCCGUAAUACUCAUCUGGAAAGCAAGCAGAGUGAACUAGACCAGGGACCUCAACGUGGUUGCACAGCUAAAAAAUAAUCAUAGGCUGUAAGAAGUCAGAACGCUAUAAAAACUUAGCAAGAAGAGUUAGAUGCCACAGACCUAUUUGAAAAACAACAACAACAACAACAAAGCUAAAUUGGCUGGACAUCUCACUCCACUAAGAGAAUCAACAAAAAGUGCUUCCAGGUUGGUGAAAUAGAGGUUCACCAGAUGAAACUGGAUGUGCAAGCAACAUCCUGUACCCCUGAAAUUAGAAUGAAGAAAUGGUAAAAUUUUGCCUUGAUCUGUAGCUUUUCCAGAACUGAAUAUUUGUCAUGGCAAGGAUCACAGACUGCCUUGCAACUAGUACUUGGAUCAAACCUUUUAUAGGAAUAAUCCCUAAGGUGAUGGCAGCACAGGGACCUUGAAACAGCAAAAGACUUAACUGGAGAAUGGAAGAAAACCUAAGGAAAGUAACCCUAAAAUCACUUCAUAGAAAAACAUCAUAAGGGAGAAAACUUCAAUUCAAGAGAAGCCCAAAAAUAAAACUCCAAGAUAGUAAACUCUCAUGGUAACAGAGACAGAAAGUGAAAUCAGCAAUUGGAAAAUAUGCUCCUGAUAAAAUAAAAAUAAUAAGUCAACUGAAAAUGUGUUUAUGUAAGUGUGUUUAUGAUCCUCAAAAACUUGAAGAAAUAUAGUUCAUAAGAAACAAAAAGAGUUAAAAAGUUCAAAAGCAGCUGAUUAAAGAAAAAUUAGGCAUAAAAACUAGUCCCUGGAAAUUUAAAAUCAAAUCCAAUUCUAAGUUAAAUACAGUAGAAGACAGAAGUAAUAAAGUGAAGGAUAUUAUUAAGGAAUUCACUCAGAAUGCAACACGGAAAGAAAAAAAGAUUAAAAAAUACAGAAGAACAGUGAUGAUAUAUGUGAUAUAUGGAUGAAUAGAUGGAAAAGCUACAAUGUAUGGCUGCUAGGAUUUCUAGAAGUCUUAGCUAAAAUAUUUUUUAAACAUAGUGAAA